AUGCACCAGGCUCUGCUACCAGUUGGUUAUUUUGGCUGUGUACUUGUGUCCAAGGUCAUUCACUCACUGGAUGCUGCUGCUGCCGGGAGCCCCGUACUAUCAGCCGUGGUUAACCCCACCGUGUUCUUCGACAUUGCUGUCAACAGCGAGCCCUUGGGCCAUGUCUCCUUCAAGCUAUUUGCAGACAAGGUUCCAAAGACAGCAGAAAACUUUCGUGCUCUGAGCACUGGAGAGAAAGGAUUUGGUUAUAAGGGUUCCUGCUUUCACAGAAUUAUUCCAGGGUUUAUGUGUCAGGGUGGUGACUUCACACACCAUAAUGGCACUAGCAGCAAGUCCAUCUACGGGGAGAAAUUUGAUGAUGAGAACUUCAUCCUAAAGCAUACAGGUCCUGGCAUCUUGUCCAUGGCAAAUGCUGGACCCAACACAAACAGUUCCCAGUUUUUCAUCUGCACUGCCAAGACUGAGUGGUUGGAUGGCAAGCAUGUGGUCUUUGGCAAGGCGAAAGAAGGCAUGAAUAUUGUGGAGGCCAUAGAGCACUUUGGGUCCAGGAAUGGCAAGACCAGCAAGAAGAUCACCACUGCUGACUGUGGACAACUCUUAAUAAGUUUGACUUGUGUUUUAUCUUAG